AUCCCUAUAGAGAAGAACGGAGGUACGGCCUGUGGUCAUGGCGCUGUUCCCAGCCUUUGCGGGGCUUAGUGAGGCUCCCGAUGGCGGGAGCUCCAGGAAAGAGUUAGACUGGCUGAGCAACCCAAGCUUUUGUGUUGGAUCCAUAACGUCCCUGAGCCAACAAACUGAAGCAGCUCCAGCCCAUGUUUCUGAAGGGUUACCGCUGACAAGGAGUCAUCUGAAAUCAGAGUCUUCAGAUGAAAGUGACACUAACAAAAAGCUCAAACAAACAAGUAGAAAAAAGAAGAAAGAGAAAAAGAAAAAAAGGAAGCAUCAGCAUCAUAAGAAAACAAAGAGGAAGCAUGGGCCGUCGAGUAGCAGCAGGUCUGAGACAGACACCGAUUCUGAAAAGGACAAACCUUCCAGAGGCGUUGGAGGCAGUAAAAAGGAAUCUGAGGAACCGAAUCAAGGAAAUAAUGCUGCAGCUGAUACUGGACAUCGCUUUGUUUGGCUUGAGGACAUUCAGGCUGUGACGGGAGAAACCUUCAGAACAGAUAAGAAACCAGAUCCUGCGAACUGGGAGUACAAGUCUCUCUACCGAGGGGAUAUAGCAAGAUACAAGAGGAAAGGAGACUCCUGCCUUGGCAUUAACCCUAAGAAGCAGUGCAUAUCUUGGGAAGGGACUUCCACAGAGAAGAAGCAUUCACGCAAGCAGGUUGAACGCUAUUUUACUAAGAAGAGUGUGGGAUUAAUGAACAUCGAUGGAGUUGCCAUUAGCAGUAAAACUGAACCUCCCUCAUCUGAGCCCAUCUCCUUUAUACCAGUGAAGGACUUGGAAGAUGCGGCUCCUGUUACAACCUGGUUGAAUCCUCUGGGGAUUUAUGAUCAGUCAACCACACAUUGGCUACAAGGACAGGGUCCUCCAGAGCAGGAAUCAAAGCAGCCAGACGCACAGCCAGACAGCGAGAGUGCGGCUCUCAAGGCCAAGGUGGAGGAGUUUAACAGGAGGGUGCGGGAGAAUCCUCGGGAUACGCAGCUGUGGAUGGCAUUUGUUGCUUUUCAGGACGAGGUCAUGAAAAGUCCUGGCCUGUAUGCCAUCGAGGAAGGAGAGCAGGAAAAGCGAAAGAGGUCCCUGAAGCUCAUUCUGGAGAAGAAGCUGGCCAUUCUGGAGCGGGCCAUUGAGAGCAACCAGAGCAGUGUGGAUCUGAAACUGGCCAAGCUGAAGCUCUGCACAGAGUUCUGGGAGCCCUCCACUCUGGUCAAAGAGUGGCAGAAACUGAUAUUUUUGCAUCCCAAUAAUACAGCCCUUUGGCAGAAAUACCUUUUAUUUUGCCAGAGCCAGUUUAGUACCUUUUCGAUAUCAAAAAUUCACAGUCUUUAUGGAAAAUGCUUGAGCACUUUGUCUGCUGUUAAGGACGGCAGCAUCUUAUCUCACCCUGCGUUGCCUGGCACGGAAGAGGCCAUGUUUGCACUCUUUCUUCAGCAGUGCCACUUUCUGCGGCAGGCUGGCCACUCUGAGAAGGCCAUCUCAUUGUUCCAGGCCAUGGUGGACUUCACCUUCUUCAAACCCGACAGCGUGAAAGAUCUGCCUACCAAAGGACAGGUGGAAUUCUUUGAACCCUUUUGGGACAGUGGAGAGCCCCGGGCUGGGGAGAAGGGAGCCCGAGGCUGGAAGGCGUGGAUGCACCAGCAGGAACGAGGUGGCUGGGUGGUCAUCAACCCAGAUGAGGAUGACGAUGAACCAGAAGAGGAUGACCAGGAAAUAAAAGAUAAGACUCUGCCCAGGUGGCAGAUCUGGCUUGCUGCUGAGCGUUCCCGUGACCAGAGGCACUGGCGGCCCUGGCGCCCUGAUAAGACCAAGAAGCAAACCGAGGAAGACUGUGAGGAUCCCGAGAGACAGGUGUUGUUUGAUGAUAUUGGGCAAUCUUUGAUCAGACUUUCCAGCCAUGAUCUUCAGUUCCAGCUGGUGGAGGCCUUCCUGCAGUUCUUGGGUGUGCCUUCUGGCUUUACUCCUCCAGCCUCCUGUCUUUAUCUGGCCAUGGAUGAGAACAGCAUCUUUGAUAAUGGACUUUAUGAUGAAAAGCCCUUGACUUUUUUCAACCCUUUGUUUUCUGGGGCUAGCUGUGUUGGCCGCAUGGAUAGGUUGGGCUAUCCUCGCUGGACCAGGGGUCAGAACCGAGAGGGCGAGGAGUUCAUCCGCAAUGUCUUCCACCUUGUCAUGCCUUUAUUUUCAGGCAAAGAGAAGUCCCAGCUCUGCUUCUCCUGGUUACAGUAUGAGAUUGCAAAGGUCAUUUGGUGCCUGCACACUAAAAACAAGAAGAGAUUAAAGUCUCAAGGGAAGAACUGCAAAAAACUAGCCAAGAAUCUCCUUAAGGAGCCAGAAAACUGCAACAACUUUUGCCUGUGGAAGCAGUAUGCACAUCUGGAGUGGUUGCUUGGCAACACGGAGGAUGCCAGAAAAGUUUUUGACACAGCACUUGGCAUGGCAGGAAGCAGAGAACUGAAAGACUCUGACCUCUGUGAGCUCAGUCUGCUCUAUGCUGAGCUGGAGGUGGAGCUGUCGCCAGAAGUGAGAAGGGCUGCCACAGCUCGAGCUGUUCACAUAUUAACCAAGCUGACUGAGAGCAGCCCCUAUGGGCCCUACACUGGACAGGUGUUGGCUGUUCACAUUUUGAAAGCGCGAAAGGCUUAUGAGCACGCACUGCAGGACUGUUUGGGUGACAGCUGUGUCUCCAAUCCAGCUCCCACCGAUUCCUGUAGCCGCCUAAUUAGCCUGGCUAAAUGCUUCAUGCUCUUCCAGUAUUUGACCAUAGGGAUUGAUGCUGCUGUGCAGAUAUACGAACAGGUGUUUGCAAAACUGAACAGUUCUGUUUUCCCAGAAGGCUCUGGCGAGGGGGACAGUGCCAGCUCCCAGAGUUGGACCAGUGUUCUCGAAGCCAUCACACUGAUGCACACGAGCCUGCUGAGAUUCCACAUGAAAGUGAGUGUUUACCCGCUGGCCCCUCUGCGAGAGGCACUCUCACAGGCUUUAAAGUUGUAUCCAGGCAACCAGGUUCUUUGGAGGUCCUAUGUACAGAUUCAGAAUAAGUCCCACAGUGCCAGCAAAACCAGGAGAUUUUUUGACACAAUCACCAGGUCUGCCAAACCCUUGGAGCCUUGGUUGUUUGCAAUUGAAGCUGAGAAACUGAGGAAGAGACUGGUGGAAACUGUCCAGAGGUUAGACGGUAGAGAGAUCCACGCCACAAUUCCUGAGACCGGCUUAAUGCAUCGGAUCCAAGCCCUGUUUGAAAAUGCCAUGCGCAGCGACAGUGGCAGCCAGUGCCCCUUGCUGUGGAGGAUGUAUUUGAACUUUCUGGUUUCCUUAGGAAAUAAAGAAAGAAGCAAAGGUGUAUUCUACAAAGCACUUCAGAAUUGCCCUUGGGCAAAGGUGUUGUACCUGGACGCCGUGGAGUAUUUCCCCGAUGAGAUGCAGGAGAUCCUGGACCUGAUGACUGAGAAGGAGCUCCGGGUGCGCCUGCCGCUGGAGGAGCUGGAGCUGCUGCUGGAGGAUUAGAGAGCAGCGGGAAAACGGGCUGUGCCUGCGAGGCCAAGUUGCCCACCCUGCGGAGCUAGGAGGCGCGAGCAGAGAACGUGUGUGUUAGGAGAACUCGGCUUUUGAAAUGUUCUUUCUCGAUAGUAAUAAUGUGGGCUGCCAGCCUCUCACAUCUUGCACACUUUUUGGGUGUGUAAAUGACACAAAAGUUAUUUACAUAUUAUAUAUGUGAAUAUGUGUAUAUAUGUACAUAGCCAGAGAGUCAUGCCACGUGGUCAUUAAACCGAUGAUGAUUGAGGCGUGGCAGCGUCCUUGCUCAUUCUCUCCCUGUGCGCAGCCAGCACUGGCCCCCGCACGGUGAAUGUGUUCCCUCCGCUGGUGUCGUGGUGGUCCUGCCAGGCCCUCUCUGAGAUAAAGGUCUGGUUUUUCAGCACUAGGAUGUCUUCCCCAGGCUGGUGAGCAGGAGAUUUUGCUCUUGUGUUGAGACCCGCAGUUAACGCUUGGUGUUCUGGCCUGCACGCAGUGUGUGGCAAGUUCCCUGAGUUUACCUCGGCGGCGAUGCCUCCGCCUGGAGCUGGAGGGGCAGCGUGCCCUGGGGCUGCUGAAAAACUCAGGCCUGUGGAGUCAGAACCCGCUCUUCAGCAGGUCCCAGGCCACUUGAGUGUGGAAGGCUGCCCGGGGCACUGGCAGCCUCUGGGGGAAGCCUGCUCCCAAGCCGUCUAGGAGCCGAGCACGCUGUACCGCCAGCCCCAGCCCUGCCUGCAUGAGGGGCCCGGCACGCUUGUGCAGCAACGCUGCUUACACUAUGAAGGCCAAGGCUGGCCUGGUUCUGGUGUUGCAUUCGAGGGCUGUGAACAGAAUGAAAUGUCAACAUCCAUUUUUCAGACUUGUUCUGCCUCCGAAGAGAUUUUUAGUGCUGAGUGAUUUUCACUAUUAACAUAUGGCUGGAAGGAAUGGUUUUCUUAUCUUCUCCGAGCUCUAGACUGGCUAGCUUCUCUCUGGCUUUUUUUGUUUUGUUUUCCUCUCUUUAGAAUUGCUGUAUACUUGUAUCUCCUCAGCACAUUUAGAAAAGCCAGUGUAUAAUUUUGGCUGGCAACUGACGGACGCAGCGGGCAGCAGCAGGCAGGGCAGCGCACGAGAGCACCUCCCAGGGCACGGUGGGAAACUGGCCAGCCCAGCCCCACUACUGCCCUCUCCUGCUCGUCCCCAGUCCCUGAGCUACAGGUGGCUGUAGGCAGAAGCCCACCGGGUGUUCCUUAGCGACAGACAGGUCGUCAGCUGCUCCCCUUGAUGCCUUUUCACAGAAACAACCCUCAACUUGAGGAAGUUGAGAGCUCCACUCCGAGGUGGACUUGCUCCCCCUCCCUGAGAGCUAACUGGCUUGAACUGUCAUGAGUUCCUGGCUGCCCACAAAGAGGGACCUUCUCCACCCUUGUCCUCUGCGUGGGGCAGACAUCAGCCAGACAUGUCACCGACCUGAUUGGGGGCAGGGAGUAGGAAGUCCAGGACCAAACCAUGCUCCCCAUGACAGCAGCUGGCGCCUCAGUCCCCAUCUGACUCAUGUCUCUUCUCAUCUGGUUCAGAACUUAGAAGGGCGUGGCCUCUGAUCAGCUGGUUCCCUCCAAACCCCAGUGGCAACCUGUCCCUUGAGAGCCAGGAAUGGCUCUUAGCAGUGGGCAGUGAGCCCCCGAGAGGAUAAAGCGGCUGCUCGAACAGAUUGCGAGCACAUUACUUGCUGCAUGGGAGGAGGUUUAAAACAAAUCAAAGAUUCCUUGAGGGCAUUUUACAGAAAACAAGAUGUCAAGAGCAUCACUGUUGUUAUUUAAAAGCCCAUUUGAGGCCAGGCGCGGUGGCUCACGUCUGUAAUCCCAGCACUUUGGGAGGCCGAGGCGGACGGAUCACGAGGUCAGGAGAUCGAGACCAUCCUGGCUAACAUGGUGAAACCCCCGUCUCUACUAAAAAUACAAAAAAUUAGCCGGGCGUGGUGGCUGGCGCCUGUAGUCCCAGCUACUCGGAAGGCUAAGGCAGGAGAAUGGCGUGAACCUGGGAGGCAGAGCUUGCAGUGAGCCAAGAUCGCGCCACUGCACUCCAGCCUGGGCGACACAGCAAGACUCCGUCUCGAAAAAAAAAAAAAAAAAACAGCCCGUUUGAGAUUGCUGACAUGAACUUCUGAAAGAUGACUACGUGCCUCCCAAGACUAACCGUCAGCUUGGAGGGCUGAGAAGGGGGUUCCCAGCUGGAGUCAAACAGUGGCUCAUGUGUUUCAUCAGGAACGCUCGUCAUUUCCCCGAAGGAGUCACUGAUCACAUCAGACCACAGGGGUCGGCCCACCUCGGGUUUGGGACAGUGUUCUUUCCUGGAAUGAAGCAGUGGCAAUGCCUCUGGCACAGGAUUGCUGGGCCUGCAGGAGGCCAGGAGGCACCUCUGUGCUGUGUUCCCAGUAGGAGGAGGCAGCUACUACUUGUAAGGCACACAUAUCAUUUUGCAUUGGAAAAGUGAAGAUAGGCUUGCUGCAGAGGGAGUGAUGGGAGAGUUCACCUUAAAUUGUUCUACUGAGGAAGGGCUCCAAAGAGCCAGUGGGUUUUCCGCAGGCAGACGGGGUUCUCCCUGUCCGGCUCACCAGUGCAGGAAGCCAGGGAAGAAAUUACUGUGGGAAUUCUGUUAUUUCACAAGCACUUCAUACCUGCAUCCCUGCACUUGGCACCGCAGGCCUCAGUGACCAGCUGCCGAAACGGUAAUUUCAGCAUUUUGGUCAGUAAGCAAACUGGAGAAGCAGCUGGGGUGGGGCGCAGUUCAGCCCGCUACCCUGACACUCUAGGCCCUGGCAUUUGCUUUAGCUGCUUUUGUAGAAUUGACAUGAGGGAGACUGUCCCUCUAGAGGAAAACGCUCAGCUAUUACCAAUGAGGAAAAGGCAAUACUGAUGUGCUGGGGUUUUUUGUUUUUUUUAAUCUCAAACUUAGGAAAAGAUGCAAGUGCGUUACAAAGAAUUUUGUUUCCUGAACCGUGUGAGUCAGUUGCUGAGAGUCUGCUACCCGCCCACGAUACAGACACUGAACAGGAAGUCAGCAUGGACGCAGUACUCCUAGCAGGUCCUCAGGCCCAGUCAUGUCCUCUAGGAAAAGGAUCCAGUUCAGGAGCAGGAGCUGCACUUGGUUGUCAUCUCUUUGGUCUCCUUCUGAUUGGAAGCUUUUUGACUUCCAAGACGUGGAUACUUUUGAAGUGUUCUGAAUUUGUAGAAUGUUCCUCAGUUUGUGUUUGCCUGGUGUUUCCUCAGCACUGGAUUCAGGCUAAGCAUCUUUGGCAGGAGUGUGACAGCACUGACACUCUUGGGUGGCACGUACUUUCAAAGUGCCCAUUACUGAUGAUGUGCAUUUGACCACUUGGUGAAGACGGUGUCUGCUGGGCAUCUCCAGUGUGACUUUCCCUUUCUAACUGAACAGUGUUUUGUGGCAGACUCUCAAAAUCUGUAAAUACCCCUUCCUCAGCAAACUUUCAGAUCAAUUCAUAUGUAUUGGGGUGUGUGUGUGUGUGUGUGUGUGUGUGUGUGUGUGUGUGUGUGUGUGUGUGUAGUUCCCUAUUUAAAGGGCUAUACUGUAUUCCAUUAAUAGUAACUGUUUGUUAGGAUGCUCAGAUUGUCCCGAGUUUGGCCAGUGGAAGCCCCUUCACAUAGGCUUCGGUGUCCUUAGGACAUGUCCUUAUCAUUCCUUGAGCACUCCCUUGCUUUCUGGCAAAACAGACUUUGGGUUCAUCCUGUCCUUUCCCUGCCUAGCCCCGGAAUCAGCCCUCACUCCUUUUAGUGGAGAAUAAUACUUUUAGCAGCAAAGGUCUGGGUCUAGGGGUGCUCACUGCAGUUGGGGUGUCACUGUUCCCAGGUGCUCCCAGUGGACAGAGGUCGUUCUUGUUUUCUUCUUUCUGUGUCUAACUCCUCAGAGAAACCUGGCUCCCACUGUCCUGUUUACCUGCCUGACUGCCUCCAUACAUAAGCAGCCUCCCUCCCCUGCCACCACCCCGUCCCUGCAGAUGCCUUCCUCACCCACUUGGGCUCUCAUACUGCACAUCAGGCUGCCCACACUGACUCCCCCUAUCGGACCACCCCAGCCCUGCACAUACACCCCACACGGAUGCCAGCCUCACCCUGCCCAUGCUGAGUCCCCGUGCUGUGGUGUUCCUCCACAUGGACAGCUCCACACCCUACUUGGGCUGACACCCGCCCUCCCCACAAGCACCCCGUCCUUACCCUGCACUGGGCCACCCCCACGUGUGGAUGUCCUCUGUGGUAGGCAGAGUGGCGCCCCUAAAGAUGGCCACACCCUAAGCCCUGGAACGUGUGAAUGUUACAUGGCAAAAGGAACUUUGCAGAUAAAAAUUAAGAAGAUUGUAAACUUUAAAACAGGGAAAUUAUCCUGGAUCAUCUGCAUGGGUCCAAUGCAAUCACAAGGAUCCAUAAGAAUAGAAAAGGCAGGCAGAAAGAAGGGUCGGUGGGAGAGAGGGACUGGGCCUGCUGCUGCUGGUGGAAAAUGAAGUGCCACGAGUCAGGAGGGAGGGUGGCCUUCACAGACUGGCAAAGGCCUCAGCUGGCAGCCAGCAAGGAAAUGCUGACCUCAGCUGGCCCACAACUCCAAGAAAUUAAAUUCUGCCAACAAUAAUCCUCAGCAAGGAAACGGAUUCUCCCUUAGAGACGCCAGAGGGAACGGUCCUGCCAACAGCAAGACUUUAGCCUGGAGACACUCGUGUUGGACUUCUGACCUACAGAACUGAGAUAAAAUUGUGGUUUUUAUUUAUUUAUUUAUUUAUUUUUGAGACGGAGUCUUGCUCUGUCGCCCAGGCUGGAGUGCAGUGACGGGAUCUUGGCUCACUGCAACCUCCGCCUCCUGGGUUCAAGCGAUUGUCCUGCCUCAGCCUCCUGAGUAGCUGGGACUACAGGCACCUGCCACCACGCACAGCUAAUUUUUGUAUUUUUAGUAAAGAUGGGGUUUCACCAUGUUGGCCAGGCUGGCCUCAAACUUCUGACCUUGUGAUCCGCCUGCCUCAGCUUCCCAAAGUGCUGGGAUUACAGGCGUGAGCCACCGUGCCUGGCCAAAUUGUGCUGUUUUUAAACAAAGCCUGUGGUAACUUGUUAUAGUAUUAACAGAAAACUAAUACACACUCCUCAUUCAGUGUGGGCCCUACAACCCACACCAGGCCACCUGUCAAGGGAACGCUUACCUUGAUCUGUCCCACUUAAUAGCUUUAGGCCUGAUUUGUUCAGAAAGAGAAAUGACGGAAAUAGACGGAGAAAGGGAAGGGGAAGUUCUGACAUGUUUCUGAACACCUUGAAAGGGAUGAGAUUUCUGAGCCCAAGGGCUCAGAAGGGCUUUCAAGAUAUCUCUAGGAAUCCUCAGUCUCUUGGGAACACCAGUAGUUAUUUUCUGCCCUCAGAGUGCUAAGAACAUGCAUGGUCCACAAAACUUCCAAAAAGGAAAGCUGUACUUCCUUUGGAAGCAAUAGCCACAUUAACGCAGCCUUUAUUAUUUAAACAACGAAUAUCCCUGGCUCUGUGGUAGUGACCAUUUCCCACUGUAAUUACCGUUGAACGCCAGCUCUGGGGGUGUGAUGUGGCGAACGCAUAGUGAGGUCCACACUCCUUGGGACCGCAGCCUGAGUUCCUGUCCAAAGGCUUCCCUGUAGCUGGGUCCACCCACAGGCUGCUGUUGAGCGGUAGGUGUGUGUGGAGACUGCAGAAACAGGAAGUGUUUGUGAAAGAGCACGCUUUAUUGGGAAGCAGACUGCUGCACAGUGACCAACAGGCCACCCAAUGGGCACUUACACAUCGUACUCCAAAAGACACAGGAUGUUUUGCUAAUAAAAAUCAGUGGGAACAGGGAUUCCUCUGGGCAACUCCCCCAACCUCAUCCCUUUCAGGGAUUGAGAAAUCUCCCAACCAUUUUCCUGAUGACAGCCAUGGUUCAUUAGAGAUACAGCCCCUCAGGGGUGCCUUCCUGUUUCUUAUAAAGAACAUUUUCUUUAGAUUUUUUGAAGUCUUCAUUUGUUACUUUCAUUCUACGUUCUCUUAAGGCCAUCAGACCAGCUUCUGUACAGAUUGCCUGUAAGAAAGAAGAGUGUGUUCAGAAAGUGACAUACUCAUUUUUAUUCUAACAAGGAAUUCCAAAAAACCUAUUCUGAGGCCAGGCGCGGUGGCUCACACCUGUAAUCCCAGCACUCUGGGAGGCCGAGGCAGGUGGAUCGCCUAAGGUCAGGAGUUCAAGACCAGCCUGGCCAACACGGUGAAACCCCAUCUCUACUAAAAAUACAAAAAGUUAGCCAGGGACGGUGGCAGGCACCUGUAAUCCUAGCUACUCGGGAGGCUGAGGCAGGAGAAUUGCUUGAACCCGGGAGGCAGAGGUUACAGUGAGCCGAGAUCGCGCCACUGCACUCUAGCCUGAGCAACGAGCGAAACUCUACCUCAAAAAAAAAAAAAAAAAAAUCUGUUCUGAAAUAAAGCAUGAGACACCUAGACUAAACACAAAUUGCUUAUUUGGGAAAGAUUUGAUUUUUAAAAAAAAUGUUUUAAGCAUCCUAUUUUCUGAAAGGAUGUGAAGUGGCUUAAACUGGGAGUUACUGUAACUAAGACUGACCCAAGGGUCAGGGCUGUGGGUUCUAGUUUUGGCUCAGGUUCUAACAAGCUAUGUGGCUUGUACAACACCACUUUUGUUAAAGAGAAUAAUAUUCCUAGGAAAUAAACAAAAUUAUGCCCUGAAACUUAGAGGCAAUUGACAGUAUAUGUCUAUUUCAUUUACUUAUAGUCAUAAAAGAACAUGUAUUCUGGUUAGAUACUGUAAGUGGCAGUAUCUAUACUAUGGAAUAAUACUACAGAGUAUAGCAUUUAUUCCAAUAUAUUUAAUUUCUCAGUAAUUACUGGCCCAAAGUAAAAGAAAACAAUAACCCAUGUUACAUGGGUUACUGUUAUUGUUUUAGGCCUGAUCUGUUUAGAAAGGAAAGAGAAAUGAAGGAAAUAGAUAGAGAAGGACAGCAAACAAACAUAUUAUGUGGGUUACUGUUAUUGUUUUCUUUUUCUUUUGGCCAGUAAUUACUGUGGCAAAAACAAGAUGUGGCAAAAAACACAAUCCUGGCACAGAAGUUUGUUUGGUGAUGGCCAUCAGGUUAUUUACUUCAAAUGGUUCGGGUGAAAAGAAAGUUUUGUGUAUAGAAAGAGAAAAAGCAAACAGGUAAAAUGUUAACUCUUGGCAAAUCACUGUGCUAUUGUUGCAACUUUUUUGAAGGCUUGAAAAUUGUCAAAGUAAGUUCUUAUCUUAAAAUUUUAAGAUCUUUCAAUUUUUAAAAAAGAAGAUAGAUUUUACUUGCCAACAGAGACAUCUAGUUCUCUAGGACUAACUGCCAAUGAUCCGUGGGCUCAGGGCAGGUGCUGGCCUGGAAAGGCACUGCUUGUGCUGUCCCUACCUAACCAUGGCAUUUAUGCCCAACGAAAACCCAGCUCUUUCCAGGAAAAGCAGGUAGAACCCAUAUUCAACGCUGCCAGACCUUGCUGUAAAUUCUGGUCAGCUGGGAGGAAAUGUCCUAACUCAUGUACAUUUGUCAUAAAACCAAGAAGUAUAAUCUGGUACAACCUUCCAGAACACAGAUUGGGAGAUGAAUGCAGCGGGUGCUUGGUCCCCACUCUGCGGCUCUGGGGAGAGUUCUCCCAGGACAUACCCUUCCCCUGACCUGGGACUGAGCAGCUACAUUUGACACACCUUGAGAAAGUCACCUGGGCCUAAGGCUUAGUACCAGCGACUCAGCCUUGUGGCUCCAGGUGAUUUAGCGUCAUUCACUGCAUAAAAUGAUGCAUUAAGAAUGACUUCAAUAUCAAGCACAUAUACCAUUUGGAUGUAAUCGUAAACCAAUAUGAUGAUUAAAAUACAGACACCCACCUGUCCAGGCCAACCACCAUCCCAAGAGCACAUAUAGACUCUUUCCUGAUUGACGGCCACAUUCCCAGAAAUAAGCUGACACGGCUAGGCUCUCACCUUGAUGUCAGCACCAGAGAGGUCAUCUUUAGCCAUGAUCAGGUCGUCCAGGGUUACAUCAUCAGCCAGCGUCAUCCUGCUUGUGUGAAUCUGAAAGAUGCGCUUCUUCGUCUUUUCAUCAGGCAGGGGGAACUCAAUCUUCCUGUCAAUGCGGCCUGCAGGUACAAAGAGAUUUGAAGUCACACCAACAUCCAAACCCAGGCUCGGCCAUGGCUCAGAGGCCUCAGCCCAUCUCCUUACAUACGAAGUUUCAGUCGGACAGAAUUCUGUGGGAAGGAUGUCUAAAUUUUAAAAAGUAAACAUAUAUUUUUGUAGUUUGUAGAUUUCUACAUUUGAAUUCUCUUCAUUUAAAAGAAACUCUCUCUGCUUUGGUACCUUCAGAAAUAAAUGAAAGGAGCAAUUCCUGAGUGAAACUGGGCAGACCUAUUGUGUUAAAAACAUUACAAAAGACAGCAAACAAAUCACUGUUUCUUCUGAUGCUACCUGAAUGUAAAAAGGACAAAUCCUACCAUCACAUGAAUUAUUUCUUCCAGAAAAAGCAGCAAGUUCUUGAGGCUAAAAAGGGAAUGUUAUGGAAAAGAAAAGACAAGACAUAAGACUGGAAUUCAAAGGGCCAAGGUGCACAGACCAUAUCAUGCUCUGUUUUAACCCUCAUCUCAAGAGGACCUAUUUUUUUGUAAAUUAUCCUAAGUUUCACUGCAGUAUUUGCUUUUUUAUGUAUCAUUUUAUAGGCCUCCCAAAGCACACUUAAACACAAAUAUAUAAACACAUUAAUCUCCAUGAUGAAACCAAAGCAAAUUUAACCUGGUCUGAUAAGUGCUGGAUCCAAAGUUUCUAUUCGGUUUGUGGCCAUGAUAACUUUCACAUCUCCCCUAGAAUCAAAUCCAUCCAACUGGUUCAGCAGUUCCAACAUUGUUCGCUGAAUUUCUCUCUCACCACCAGAAUUGGAGUCAUAUCUUUGGAAAAAAAAAAAGGGAAGGAAUGAAGACUCAACUGAUCGCCUGCUCAAGGGGAAUUACAGCAAAGACCUCAUUGUGACAAAACACCUUAACAAACAUUCCUGUUUCAACUCACAUGGCACUCCCUCAAUUAUGCUCGGAAAAAAUAAAUUCAGCACCCCUUGCCAUGGUCUGAAUGUAUUUCCCCAAAUUUAUGUGUUGAAACUUAAUCCCUACUGUGUGGCUAAGAGAUGAGGCCUUUUGGAAAGGGCUAAAGGCAUGAGGCAGAGCCUUAUACAGCAUGAGUUCCUUCUAAAAAGAGAAAAAGGCCUUAUACAGCAUGUAUUCCUUAUAAAAAAUGCUGCAGGGAACUAGUGUAGGCCCUUUUUGCUCUUUUGUUUGUCCCCUGAGCAUUUGUCUCCUCUGCAGAAUAGGUGCCAUCUCGGAAGCAGAGAGCAGCCCUCACUAGACAUCAAUGCCAGUGCCUUGAUCUUGGGCUUCUCAGCCUCCAGAACUGUGGGAAAUACAUUUCUAUUCUUUAUACAAAUACCAGUCCUAAGGUAUUUUGUUUAGCAGCACAAAUGGACUAAGACGCUCCCAUCAGCCAAGUUACAGAUCAUAUUUUUUCAUAGCAGUUUCUGUGUCUGAAAUUGUAUCAUUUAUUCUGUUUCCAUGUUUGGUAUCUGAUCCCUACAACCUGUGAGCUCCUCCAGGGCAGAGACUUGUGCUCACAACUGUGUCCCUAGAGUCCAGAUGGUCCUGGAUCAGGGCGGGUGCUCAAGACAUGGUUAUUCAUAACUGACCAAUCUCUCCAGACGUUCACAGUUACUGGGCAGUUGUUAGCUGGCUCCUGGGAGAGCAGAGCCUAAAGCAUGCAUGGAAGGCCACGCACAGCAAGAACUGUGGCCAUAGGGAGAGCCCCCUGAGAUUGCUCAUUCUCAAGAGAAGAGCUAUGCGGUGUUCCCUACUAAACAAGGCAAAAUAAGUAUGAGAAAGUCUACCUUUUUGUCCCAAUGGCGUCAAUUUCAUCAAUAAACACGAUGGACGGUGCAUGUUCUUCAGCAACUCGGAACAAUUCCCGUACGAGUUUGGGCCCAUCACCUAGGUACUUCUGAAUAAGUUCAGAGCCAACCACUCUCAAGAAAGUGGCUGAGGUUUGGUUUGCUACUGCUUUGGCUAACAAGGUUUUACCUAUUUUGGAUGAAAAAGAUAAAAAAAAAAAAGACACCUUAAGUGCCAUUUUAACUUAAAAACUCGUAUCAUUACCACCUUAAAUGGACACCAAAAACAGGCGGGCCCUCAUGCUAAGGCAUGGCACCAAUUCAAGUGUCACGACAUUCCAUUCUCCUAAGUAGAUAAGAGGACAUUUAGAAAAAUCUACUAACAUGUUUGGAUUAUCCUUAGCUAUUUUGCUGAACUUAUGAUAACGUCAGAAAAUACUUUUUACUUGGUUAUUUUCCAACCUUGACCCAGUUUCCCCUGAAAAGCUGCGAACUAUAAUUACCUGUACGAAGAAUUGCUUCAUUCCAGUAAUGAAAUAAAUCUCAUUUUUUUC